AUUGUGCCUCGGACAACGAGUGUACGCAGUUACCACACAGUUACCAAGCAGUUACCUCAGAGCCGCGGCGCAGACGUAGGCCUCAGGUCUCGGGCCUCAGGUCUCGGGCCUCAGAGCCAGACCCCGCCAUCUCACGAUGUCAGAGAGGACCCAGGAACAGGAUUUUGUUAUUAUAACUGUCGACGACAGUGAUGAUAACAAUGAUUGCAGUAUUGAGAUGGUGGAAGUUUCUGAAACAGCAGAUAAUUCCACUAAUGACAUAGCAGAUGAUUCCACUUAUGUCACAGCAGAUAAUCCCACUGAUGACACAGCCACACAACCAAAUUUUCCAGGCGGCAAUGAUGGCCAUCACCGUCCACUCCAAAUGUCAUAUGGGUCUGGCUCUGUCACCCAGGCUGGAGUGCAGUGGCAUGAUCACAGCUCACUGCAGCCUCAACCUCUUGGACUCAAGCAAUUCUUCCACCUCAGCCUUCCCAGUAGCUGGGAUGACAGGCGCACGCCACCAUGCCCAGUAGCCCAUGGUGACCAAAUAGUUUCACAGAUAAACCACCCAGUACAUUUAAGAAGAUACAGUUACAACUCAGAGGAAGUGGAUUUUCCAAAAAGAGGAAGAUUCUAUACUCCAGAGGUACAGUCUAGCAUAUCACCACCAGCGGAAAGGCAGGAAACCCAUGCCUGGGCCAGCCCUGCUGUAACAUCUCUUGAGUCAGCAGCAUGUCAUGAACUGCAGGAAGCAGACCUCAGUGAGAGUUUAUCAUAUCCCAGAAUUGUCUCCUCAAGUUCAUUACAGCAGUAUGUCGCACAAGGUGGCUCAUUUCCUUGUUUCGGUAUGCCAUGGAACUUUAUCAGUGGAGGUGCUGAAAGUACCAAUGCUGUCAUCUCAUUUGCCAAUGCUACUACAGCAGUACCUAUGGCAGUUCUGUCACGAAGAGAAUCCAGUCUGGCAAAUAACCCUGGUGUGGUGAAUUACUCUGCUCUACCAGAAAAUGAAAAUGUGGGCCCAGGUAGAGCCUUGUCAUCUUUCUGCUUCCAUCCCAAUUUGGAAAUGCCAGAAAGACCAGCAAACAGCAGUAAAAACAGCACUGAGACAGCGAAUUAUCCAACUUUAAUGGGAAAUUACAAUGGCCAAAAUACUGCCUCUUUAUCUGUCUUCAUCCCUCCCUAUUUUGCUGAGAAAAUUAUACUUACUGAAAUGCCAGGAACAACAGAAACCAACGUGGAAAAUAACUCUCAGACAGUGUAUUACCCAGCUUUAUCGGGAAAUACGAGUGCCCCAUAUCCAGCCUCUUCAUAUCUUCCCAUCACUUCUAAUUUUGCACUGCAAAAUGUUUUACAUAUUGAAAUGUUGUUCAAAACAGAAUCUGGCCCACAAAUGAGUUAUGGGACAAUGAGUUACUCAACUGAAAUGAAAAAUAACUGUGACCAAGAUGAUGCUUCAGCAUCUGCCUGCCUCACUCCCGAUUUUGCACUGUUACCUCUGAAUAUUUUGGUAAAAGUAGACACCAACACGGAAAACAGCGUCAACACAAUGAAUCGCUCAACUUUAUUGGACAGUGACAGUGGCCAGGAUUCUUCCUCAUCAUCUGUCUGUAUCCCUCCCAAGUAUGGCUAUCUUGGUGAUCCAAAAAGAAAUGUCAGAGUACUUAAAAUCCAUUUGCUGGCCGUACAAAAUAUGGCCAAACCUAAGCAAGCAGCCUGCUACUUGGUUCGUAUUUUGUUCUCCAAGGAAAUCCUGAUUAGCAGCUCAGUGGAUAUCCAUUUGAAAGACAGCCAAUCCCUCGACCCGAACAAAAUGGCUGCAUUGAGAGAAUAUCUGGCAACAACUUUUCCCACCUGUGAUUUGCAUGAACAUGGAAAAGACUGGCAGGACUGUAUUUCUGGUAUCAAUUCUAUGAUCUACUGUUUAUGUUCUGAAGGCAAGAGUACUCCAAAAACUGUUCGCAAAAAUAAAAAACGUACCAACCGUGUUGCAUCGGCAUCUGCAGAUAGAAAUGACCAAAGGGGCAGAGAUGGUGGUGAAGGCUGUUCUUGGAUGUUUCAGCCAAUGAAUAACUCCAAAAUGAGAGAAAAGAGGAACUUGCAGCCAAACAGUAAUGCUAUCCCUGAAGGAAUGCGAGAACCUUCCACUGAUAAUCCAGAGGAACCUGGUGAAGCAUGGAGCUAUUUUGGAAGACCAUGGAGAAAUAUACGGAUGCCAUGUUCAGUACUGACUUUGGCAAAAACUAAGUCUUGCGCAAGCCUGUCGGCUAGAUACCUUAUUCAGAAACUCUUCACAAAAGAUGUCCUGGUCCAAAGUAACGUCUAUGGCAAUCUGAAGCAUGGCCUGUGUGCCCUUGACCCCAAUAAGAUUAGUGCUCUCCGAGAGUUCCUCCAAGAAAACUACCCAAUUUGUGAUCUCUCGGAAAAUGGAAGAGACUGGAAGUCGUGUGUGACCUCCAUCAACAGCGGUAUCCGUAGCCUUAGACAUGACGUCAGAAGGGCUGAAGCCAGGUCUCAGUCGCUUCCAGCAGUGACCCCUCCAGAGCUGGAGCAGGAGUCAAAGCCAGGAGAUCCCGACGCCACUGACCCAAGCACCUGAACGGCAGCUGCCAAACUUUUUUUUUUUUUUUAACUGUUAAGACUAUUUUGUAAGUUUCUCAAGUUCUAAUUCCAAAAUCAGCCUGCUGUACUGGCAGAGUAGUUUGCAUUGACACCUGUAGUAAUCGCCAAACCUCUUUUUCUGCUCAUAAAGGAGGUAGAAUCACAUUAGGAAGAUACGUAAUGUUUCAUCUGUGGAUUUGAUGACAACCUCUGAUUGAGGGAAUGGUAGUAAACUCCUCAUGGGCUUGUGACCCAUGGCUUUGACUUAGAUAAUUGACAUUAAUAUACUUUGUUUUUUUGAUAAGGUAGAGAAAGAAAUUCAAUAGAAAGUAAGGAGCCACUCAGUCAAAUAAUAUAAUUCGUAUAAAACUUGACAAGUCUUUUUAUUUUUGUGACUUGUGAGAUAGUUUAAGAUAUUUUUAUGUGACCAAUUUGUAGAAUGAAUACAUAUUUUCAAAGUUAUCUUUUCAAAAUUCAACUUUUAGAGUAUUUUAGCAAAAUAUAUGUAUAGUUUAUAAUAUAGAAGUAUAGCUUUAUAAAGAUAUUAAGGAUUUAUUUUUUAAAAUAAUUCUCUGAAUAGUUUGCUGUAGUAGUUGCCUUCAGCUUAAUAAAACCAUAGUACUUCUACAUACAUCUUUAUAAGUUAGGCUAUGCCUACAAAGGUCUUAAAAAGUAGAUAAUUUACCGGGUGUAGUGGCUCACACCUGUAAUCCCAGCACUUUGGGAGGCCGAGACGGGUGGAUCACCUGAGGUCAGGGGUUCGAGACCAGCCUGGCCAACAUGACGAAACCCCAUCUCUACUAAAAAUACAAAAAAAGUAGCCAGGCAUGGUGGCAAGCACCUGUAGUCCCAGUUACUCGGGUGGCUGAGGCAGGAGAAUCACUUGAACCUGGGAGGUGGAGACUGCAGUGAGCCGAGAUUGUGCCACUGCACUCGAGCCUGGGUGACAGAGUGAGACUCCGUCUCGGGAAAAGAAAAAAAAGAAGUAGAUAAUUAAAAAAAUCUUGCAUAAAAAAAAAUCUUCCAUAAAGGGCAAAAAGGCUUUAACUUCCAUUAUUCAGAUUUAAUCCAACUAAGAUAGUCUUUGGCUUCAUUCACUGUUCAGUUUCACAAGUUUUUUACAACUACUAGUAACAGAGCUAAUACAGAAUAGUAAUCCACAUUAUAAACAUAGAUCAAAAUACCACAUCAUACCCCAUAAAUACAUGCAGUUAUUAUUUGUCAAUUAAAAAUAAAAUUUUUUUAAAAGAAAAGUACAGUUCGACCCUAGGCAAGAAGAAAUUUCAAAUUGUAUAUGCAUAUUUUGAAUUUGGUUUAUAUUUUGUGGUAUCUGAAAUAUUCCCUGGACUAGAAGCAAAACCACAGAAACAAAACUUUACAUUUAGAAAAAAAUUUCAAGACUUCUAUUGCUAACUUUAUUACAUUAGUGGUUUUUAGAAGUUAUUUAGAGCAGUCUUGUCUGAUAGAACUUUCCACCAUGAUGGAAAUGUAAAUAAAUAUACCACAUUAAAAAUAUAAAUUUGCAAUGUCCAAUAGGCUCGUAUGGCUAUUGAGCAUUUAAGAUGUAAUUAAUUAGACAGAGGAAGUAAAUUUAACAUUUUCUCUCAUUUUAGCUAAUUAGAAUUUAAAGUGAAAUAGCCACAAGUGGAUAGUGGCUACUGUGUUGGAUGGCACAGUUCAAAAUGCCUCUUAUUUAUAAAAAAAAGUGUUUAAAAGUGGUUCCCAUGGCUUGAAGAGGAAUAAUAUACACAUAACUUCUUUAAAAUCACAUUUUGUUUGAGAUGGAGAUCUUGCUAUAUUGCCCAGGCUUAUCUGGAACUCCUGGGCUCAAGAGGGAGGAUCACAUUUGACUGGACAAAAUACAUUUUAUAAAGGUGUUUUGUAUUUUAUGUUAAAGUGGAAUUGUGUCUUCAAAAUUGUGUCUUCAAAAUUUCACAAGUUAAUACUAUUACUGUAUUAGUCCAAUGUUAAACAUUUUAAAUGCCUGCUCAUAAGACUCAUUUUUGAUAAAUAAAUGUAUCUUUAAUGUUUUGUUUCCCAAAUAGAUACAAUAAAUAAACAUUUAAAAUGCCUUAA